GAGGGUGAGAAGGGCCGGCUGCCGGAGCUGGGUUGCGAUCUUCCCGGAGCCGGAGACCCUCCCUUGAAACCGGCACUGGGACUUCUCGAUCUCUGGAGGCACCUGUUGCAAGUGACAGCGCUCGGCCGUCGAGCGGGGUCGCUAACCCGCACUCUCUUCGGACCUACGACAUCGCGGCUUCUCUGGCGUUGGCCAGUCAGCCACAGAGACUGAGUCGCCCUGUGUUGCCCAGGCUGGUCUUGAACUCCUAGGCUCAAGAGAUCCUCCUGCCUCAGCCUCCCAAAGUGCUGGGAUUACAGGCAACUCUGGUAGCUCUCCUUGUCUGGUUGUUUUGAAGAAAGAAGAGUAGAAGAAAAAGUUGAGUAAAUCAUGUCGGAGUUACUGGACCUUUCUUUUCUGUCUGAGGAGGAAAAGGAUUUGAUUCUCAGUGUUCUACAGCGAGAUGAAGAGGUCCGGAAAGCAGAUGAGAAAAGGAUUAGGCGACUAAAGAAUGAGUUACUGGAGAUAAAAAGGAAAGGGGCCAAGAGGGGCAGCCAACACUACAGUGAUCGGACCUGUGCCCGGUGCCAGGAGAGCCUGGGCCGUUUGAGUCCCAAAACCAAUACUUGUCGGGGUUGUAAUCACCUGGUGUGUCGGGACUGCCGCAUACAGGAAAGCAAUGGUACCUGGAGGUGCAAGGUGUGCGCCAAGGAAAUAGAGUUGAAGAAAGCAACUGGGGACUGGUUUUAUGACCAGAAAGUGAAUCGCUUUGCUUACCGCACAGGUAGUGAGAUAAUCAGGAUGUCCCUGCGCCACAAACCUGCAGUGAGUAAAAGAGAGACAGUGGGACAGUCCCUCCUUCAUCAGACACAGAUGGGUGACAUCUGGCCAGGAAGAAAGAUCAUUCAGGAGCGGCAGAAGGAGCCCAGUGUGCUAUUUGAAGUGCCAAAGCUGAAAAGUGGAAAGAGUGCAUUGGAAGCUGAGAGUGAGAGUCUGGAUAGCUUCACAGCUGACUCGGAUAGCACCUCCAGGAGAGACUCUCUGGAUAAAUCUGGCCUCUUUCCAGAAUGGAAGAAGAUGUCUGCUCCCAAAUCUCAAGUAGAAAAGGAAACUCAGCCUGGAGGUCAAAAUGUGGUAUUUGUGGAUGAGGGUGAGAUGAUAUUUAAGAAGAACACCAGAAAAAUCCUCAGGCCUUCAGAGUACACUAAAUCUGUGAUAGAUCUUCGCCCAGAAGAUGUGGUACAUGAAAGUGGCUCCUUGGGAGACAGAAGCAAAUCCGUCCCAGGCCUCAAUGUGGAUAUGGAAGAGGAAGAAGAAGAAGAAGACAUUGACCACCUAGUGAAGUUACAUCGCCAGAAGCUAGCCAGAAGCAGCAUGCAAAGUGGCUCCUCCAUGAGUACGAUCGGCAGCAUGAUGAGCAUCUACAGUGAAGCUGGUGAUUUCGGGAACAUCUUUGUGACUGGCAGGAUUGCCUUUUCCCUGAAGUAUGAGCAGCAAACCCAGAGUCUGGUUGUCCAUGUGAAGGAGUGCCAUCAGCUGGCCUAUGCUGAUGAAGCCAAGAAGCGCUCUAACCCAUAUGUGAAGACUUACCUUCUGCCUGACAAGUCCCGCCAAGGAAAAAGAAAAACCAGCAUCAAGCGGGACACUAUUAAUCCACUAUAUGAUGAGACGCUGAGGUAUGAGAUCCCAGAAUCUCUCCUGGCCCAGAGGACCCUGCAGUUCUCAGUUUGGCAUCAUGGUCGUUUUGGCAGAAACACUUUCCUUGGAGAGGCAGAGAUCCAGAUGGAUUCCUGGAAGCUUGAUAAGAAACUGGAUCAUUGCCUCCCUUUACAUGGAAAGAUCAGUGCUGAGUCCCCGACUGGCUUGCCAUCACACAAAGGCGAGUUGGUGGUUUCAUUGAAAUACAUCCCAGCCUCCAAAACCCCUGUUGGAGGUGACCGGAAAAAGAGUAAAGGUGGGGAAGGGGGAGAGCUCCAGGUGUGGAUCAAAGAAGCCAAGAACUUGACGGCUGCCAAAGCAGGAGGGACUUCAGACAGCUUUGUCAAGGGAUACCUCCUUCCCAUGAGGAACAAGGCCAGUAAACGUAAAACUCCUGUGAUGAAGAAGACCCUGAAUCCUCACUACAACCAUACAUUUGUCUACAAUGGUGUGAGGCUGGAAGAUCUACAGCAUAUGUGCCUGGAACUGACUGUGUGGGACCGGGAGCCCCUGGCCAGCAAUGACUUCCUGGGAGGGGUCAGGCUGGGUGUUGGCACUGUUAACAUUCAGCCAAUACUUAUUGAGUGCCUACUAUGUGCCAGGACUAGGGGAAGGCUGAGCUCAUGCACUGAUAUGUGCACAGAUAAAUGUGACCCUGAUUGCCAGGAACUUCAUAAUCUUCCCACCAAAAAAAUCUACAAACCUACCUAUAUGGAUCAGUAAUGGGGAAGUGGUGGACUGGAUGGACUCGACUGGGGAAGAAGUGAGCCUGUGGCAGAAGAUGCGACAGUACCCAGGGUCUUGGGCAGAAGGGACUCUGCAGCUCCGUUCCUCAAUGGCCAAGCAGAAGCUGGGUUUAUGAGUCCCUGUCCUCUUCUGCAGGUCCAGCCCUGGCGAGGGCAGGUCAGAGGAAGUGAAGAAAUCAAGAGCAAAGAUUUAUAAUUUAAUGUGUAUGUGUGUAUGUGUGUAUGUGUGUGUGUGUGUGUGUGUGUGUAUGUGUACAAACAUGUAUUUUCUGCAAAUCUCAUUAUGCUGGCUAGAGUGAUGCAGACUUGUUCUUCUUUUUAAAGCAGUCUCAAGAAUAAGCAUUUCUUUAAAAUGUUUCUGUGUAUAAUCUAGUUUAUUUUCAGAGUCCAUUUUUUCUUAUGUCUUUAUAAGGUUCACUUAACUUAAAAACAGCUUUUAAAACAACUUUUUAUCUUCUGUCUUGCUAUCAUUGUUCCUACUUCCCUAGGAAGCCCUGGCUACCUUUCGCAUUAGGACCAGUCUGGGUUUUAAGGCUCUGGGAAGCAGGGUUGGUUAGUAAAGACAGGAAUGUUGGGGAGAGGUGAGUAGUUCCUUCCUCUUUCUCCUCUCCAAUUUAUGCUUUUAACUUAUUUUCUACCUGGAUAAACUUCUGGAACUUGGCUUUUAAAUUUAACUUUUCUAGUUUUUAAGCAGUUUCCACCUUGCUUUGGUCUAAUGCUUUUCUUUGAAAUGCUAACAGAAUUCCCAAGCUUUUUCCAGUUCUAGAUAUCUUUACUAGACCUUUGGGGGACUCUUAUAAUGGAGCUGCUUUUGAAAAGCACUUUAAUUAGAUAAUGUAUUUUGACUAAAUCACGAGGAUGCCCAGUGAGAGCUUCUAGCUGAUCUCAGAGGACCAGAGUGACUGAGGGUAAAGUGUCUCACAGCCCAUGCUGAAUUUUCUGCAUUUUAAACUGAUACUGCAGUCAUUGGAGAGAGAGCUCCUCAUUUCUCGAAUGAAAGAUGAGAUAUAUUCAUCCUCAUGUACCACAUCUGUCUUAGUGUUUGCGUCUGGGGUGUGUUAUCAAACAGAGCAUGGUCUACAUCCCACUGUGUCAACCAGAAGAGCCAAGUGUUAUCUCAAUUGGCCCAGUGUUUCUCCAGGCUGGGGACUGUUAAGGGCUCUAAGGGAAUGUAGACAGAGUCUCCCUGUUAUUCUGACUUCCUGCUUGAUGAGCUUUCAGUUCCUGUUUUUGCUAUUGUUUCCUAAAUUUGACCUACAUAUUACAUGGGUGUAGUGUGUUGAGGCUUUUCAAAGAAGGGUCUAGUGAGCUAAGUUUCAUCUUCUGGUACUCAUUGAUCAAACUGACCUUUCUAUUCUCAUAAGCGUUUCUACCCAAAGUUGUGUGUGGAAGGAGUGUAUAGCAGAGAGGAAAUCCCUUUCAACAGAGUCAGCUGCUAACUGAUUUCCUAUAAGCACACUGGAUUAAGGGCAGCCACAGUGGUUUCUACUGUAUGUAUGAACCGAAUGGAGGAAUGUUUUCAAAGAUUGAUUUGGUGUGGAUUGCAAUUGUAAUGGAAGGCAUAACUUGGGAUCCCGGGCUGUAACUUGCUCUUUUGUUUCCCACCCCCCUGACAUGUAUGUGUGCUUUAAUAAAGCUUUCUCACUUGUCAAA